CCCUUUAGCUGCCAUCUUGCGUCCCCGCGUGUGUGCGCCUAAUCUCAGGUGGUCCACCCGAGACCCCUUGAGCACCAACCCUAGUCCCCCGCGCGGCCCCUUAUUCGCUCCGACAAGGUACAAAAAGGCUCUGGACGGCGGCGUGGUAGGAGGACGGGAGCGGGGGCGGGAAGUUCCCUGAAGGAGCGAGACAGGGAGGGACAGGGCAGAGGAGGAGAGGAAGGCGAUGCGACGGACAGGCGCACCCGCUCAGGCUGACUCUCGGGGGCGAGGUCGAGCCAGGGGCGGCUGCCCUGGGGGCGAGGCGACGCUGUCUCAACCUCCACCUCGCGGCGGAACCCGAGGACAGGAGCCUCAGAUGAAAGAAACAAUCAUGAACCAGGAAAAACUCGCCAAACUGCAGGCACAAGUGCGCAUUGGUGGGAAAGGAACUGCUCGCAGAAAGAAGAAGGUGGUUCAUAGAACAGCCACAGCAGAUGACAAAAAACUUCAGUUCUCCUUAAAGAAGUUAGGGGUAAACAAUAUCUCUGGUAUUGAAGAGGUGAAUAUGUUUACAAACCAAGGAACAGUGAUCCACUUUAACAACCCUAAAGUUCAGGCAUCUCUGGCAGCGAACACUUUCACCAUUACAGGCCAUGCUGAGACAAAGCAGCUGACAGAAAUGCUACCCAGCAUCUUAAACCAGCUUGGUGCGGAUAGUCUGACUAGUUUAAGGAGACUGGCCGAAGCUCUGCCCAAACAAUCUGUGGAUGGAAAAGCACCACUUGCUACUGGAGAGGAUGAUGAUGAUGAAGUUCCAGAUCUUGUGGAGAAUUUUGAUGAGGCUUCCAAGAAUGAGGCAAACUGAAUUGAGUCAACUUCUGAAGAUAAAACCUGAAGAAGUUACUGGGAGCUGCUAUUUUAUAUUAUGACUGCUUUUUAAGAAAUUUUUGUUUAUGGAUCUGAUAAAAUCUAGAUCUCUAAUAUUUUUAAGCCCAAGCCCCUUGGACACUGCAGCUCUUUUCAGUUUUUGCUUAUACACAAUUCAUUCUUUGCAGCUAAUUAAGCCGAAGAAGCCUGGGAAUCAAGUUUGAAACAAAGAUUAAUAAAGUUCUUUGCCUAGUAUACAGUUUUAUUUUUUUAUUUCAUUGACACCGAUCUGUACACAGUAAAAAAAAUUGCUUAUAGAAAGCUAAUCAUGGCAUGUAAUAUGGCUGAUAACCUUUGGAAUUUGAUUAAAGAUUUAAAAUCACGGUGUAGUGUAACAAAGGUGGUAUAAAGUUCUCAGGUUUGAAAA